UUUUUUUUUUUUUUAUUUUUUUAUUUUUUAUUUUUUAUUUUUUAUUUAUUUUUUUUAUUGAUCAUUCUUGGGUGUUUCUCGCAGAGGGGGAUUUGGCAGGGUCAUAGGACAAUAGUGGAGGGAAGGUCAGCAGAUAAACAAGUGAACAAAGGUCUCUGGUUUUCCUAGGCAGAGGACCCUGCGGCCUUCCGCAGUGUUUGUGUCCCUGGGUACUUAAGAUUAGGGAGUGGUGAUGACUCUUAACAAUUCUUUCAGUUUUUCUACAUAGACAAUCAUGUCACCUGUGAACCAAAACAGUUUUCUUUCUUCUCAAUCUGUAUAUUUUUUAUUUCCUUUCCUUGUCUUAUUGCAUUAGCUAGAACUUAGAGGAUGAUGUUGAAAACCAGUGUUGAGAGGGAACAUUCUUACCUUGUUCCUGAUUUUAGUGGGAAGGUGUCAACUUUUUCACUAAUACGUAUGAUGUUAGCUGUAGGUUUUUUGCAGGUGUUCUUUAUCACGUUGAGGAAAUUCUCCUCUAUUUGCCUUUUGUUUGUACACUCCUUUCUCCUAAAAACUGAUCUUUUGAAGACUGCCUUUUUGCAUCUUGCAUCCUCUUUAUCUGUAAUCAACUCUGAACUAGCAGGACGCUUUUUAAGUAUUUUCAUACAUAAUGUGAUUUUAUGUCAAUCUUUUAUCUGCUGCUCGUUUCCUUCUUUUUUUAUUCUGCACAGUUUUCCUGAACUGCCCUUGAUCUUCAUGAAGAUUUAUGGCUGGAGCAUAAGGAUGUACUAGGAUUUAAAUUUCUACUUAUGUUCUGUGCCUUUUAGUUAUACUGAGAGCUUGAGCUUUACGUAGCUUCAUUUUUUUUGUCAGUCUUUGUGUCCUGUGAAUUCACUAAUAUCCCAUCACUUUUAUUUUUUAAUUUUUAUUUUUAUGUUUUAUUUUUGAGACAGAGUCUCGCUCUCUCGCCUAGGCUGGAGCGCAGUGGUGCGAUCUUGGCUCUCUGCAACCUCCGCCUCCCGGGUUCAUGCCAUUCUCCUGCCUCAGCCUCCCGAGUAGCUGGGACUACAGGCGCCUGCCACCAUGCCCGGCUAAUUUUUUUGUAUUUUUAGUAGAGAUGGGGUUUCACCACAUUAGCCAGGAUGGUCUCGAUCUCCUGACCUCGUGAUCUGCCCACCUCGGCCUCCCAAAGUGCUAGGAUUACAGGCCUGAGCCACCACGCCCGGCCAUCCCAUCACUUUUAUUUUGUAGAUUCAGCAGGAUUUUCUAGUUAGACAGUCAUACCAUCUACAUUCUUUUUGUUAUUUAUGUUUUUAUUUCUUUUUCUUGCUCUGUUGCAUUGACUAUAGUGAAACUUGUGAUUUUCAAUUUCAAGUUCACGAAUUUUCAAUUUUUUAAAUUAUUGAUUGGUUUAUUAUUAUUUUUUUUUGAGACAGGUCUCACUCUGUCACCCAGGCUGUAGUGCAGUGGUGCGAUCUUGGCUCACUGUAACCUCCUCCUUGAGGGUUCAAGUGAUUCUUGUGCCUCAGCUCCUGAGUAGCUGGAAUUAGAGGCGCGUGCCACCACACUGGCUCAUUUUUUAAAUAUUUUUAGUAGAGAUGGGGUUUUACCAUGUUGCCAGGCUGGUCUUGAACUCCUGACCUCAAAUGAUCCACCCACCUUGGCCUCCUAAAGUGCUGGGAUUACAGACUUGAGCCACUGCCCAGCCUAUUUUUUAUUUUUUUUUUAGAUGGAGCUUGCUCUGUCACCCAGGCUGGAGUGCAGUGGCACGACCUCAGCUCACUGCAGCCUCCAUCUCCCAGGUUCAAGUGAUUCUCCUGCCUCUGCUUCCCAAGUAGCUGGGAUUACAGGCACAUGCCACUAUGCCCAGCUAAUUUUUGUAUUUUUAGUAGAGACGGGGGUUGACUGCAUUGGCCAGGCUGGUCUUGAACUCCUGACCUCAAGUGAUCUGCCUGCCUUGGCCUCCCAAAGUGCUGGGAUUACAGGUGUGAGCCACUGUGCCCGGCUCAAAUUCACAAAUUUGAAUUCACACUAGAAGUGUGAAUGGAUAUUCUAGCUUUGUCCUUCAGGACAAGGGGAAAAUGUUCCAUCUUUAAACAUUAAGUAUGAUGAUGUUUCAUUAUAUGACCUUUAUCAUAUUGAGGAAGUUAUCUGAGUGUUUUUAAGCAUGAAUAGAUGUUGAAUAUUGUCAAAUGCUUGAAAUGCACCGAUUACAAUCUUCCAUUCUGUCCCGUUGGUCUAUACAUAUGUCUUCAUGCUAGUUCCACAGUUUUGGUUACAAUAGCUUUGUAGUAAAUUUUGAAACCAGCUUUUCAAAGCUGAUUGAAGUCCAGUUUAAUUCUUGUGUUUCAAGAUUAUGUUGUCUGUUCUGAGUCCCUUGAGAUUGCUAAUGAAUUUUAUGGUUGAUUUUGCUACUUACGCAAAAAACAUCGUUGGGUUUUUUUAGGGAUUGCAUUAAAUCUGUAGAUAGUUUUGGGUGGUACGAAGAUCUUAAUAUUAAGUCUUGCAAUCCAUGAACAUGAAUUGUGUUUUCUAUUAUUUGUCUCUUUGAUUUUUUCUGCAAUAUUUUAUACUUUUCAGUUAGUCAUAUUUUCUAUAAAUUUAAAGAAAAGAAAUUAAUGUAUAUGCACUCUCAUUUUUACUAUUUUUCUUUUCAGUUAUGUCUUCAUUCCUUUACUAUAUCCAAUUUUUCUUUUCUUUUUGUCUGAAGAACUUUAACGUUUCUUGUAGUGAAGGUUUGAGAAUUAGAUCAGAGUCCUGGAAGCCAAGUGAAUGAAGUAUAUCAAGAAGAUGGAAGUGCUCAACCUUGCUGAUCGGUGAAGAAAUAGGAGGAAUAAGAAUUGACCCUUAGAUUUAAUAACUUGUAGUAUGAAGUCUUUUCUGAUGAAAACAAAUGAUUAUUAGUCAAGGAAUUCGCAAAGGAAAUUCAGUUCAGCCAUCCUUUUGGAUCUCAUGGAUUUCUAAAUUUGACCAAGAGAACACUUCAGUUAUGGAAGAUCAAAAUGAAGAUGAGUCCCCAAAGAAAAAUACUCUUUGGCAGAUAAGUAAUGGAACAUCAUCUGUGAUCGUCUCCAGAAAGAGGCCAUCAGAAGGAAACUAUCAAAAAGAAAAAGACUUGUGUAUUAAAUAUUUUGACCAGUGGUCUGAAUCAGAUCAAGUGGAAUUUGUGGAACAUCUUAUUUCACGAAUGUGUCAUUAUCAGCAUGGACAUAUUAACUCUUACCUGAAGCCCAUGUUGCAGCGGGACUUUAUUACCGCUUUACCAGAGCAAGGCUUAGAUCACAUAGCAGAAAACAUUCUUUCGUACCUGGAUGCCAGGUCUCUGUGUGCAGCAGAGCUGGUAUGUAAAGAAUGGCAGCGAGUGAUCUCAGAAGGAAUGCUUUGGAAGAAGCUGAUUGAACGAAUGGUACGCACUGAUCCCCUAUGGAAAGGACUUUCAGAAAGAAGAGGGUGGGAUCAGUACCUGUUUAAAAACAGACCCACAGAUGGCCCUCCAAAUUCAUUUUAUAGGUCAUUAUACCCAAAGAUUAUCCAGGAUAUAGAGACUAUAGAAUCUAACUGGCGGUGUGGACGACACAACUUGCAGAGGAUUCAGUGCCGCUCUGAAAAUAGUAAAGGUGUCUACUGUUUACAGUACGAUGAUGAAAAAAUUAUCAGUGGCCUACGAGAUAAUUCUAUUAAGAUAUGGGAUAAAACCAGCCUGGAAUGUUUGAAAGUGUUAACAGGACACACAGGCUCUGUCCUCUGUCUGCAGUAUGAUGAGCGUGUCAUUGUAACUGGCUCUUCAGAUUCUACGGUGAGAGUGUGGGAUGUGAACACGGGUGAAGUUCUUAACACAUUGAUCCACCACAAUGAGGCUGUAUUGCACUUACGCUUCAGCAAUGGACUGAUGGUGACCUGUUCCAAGGACCGCUCCAUUGCUGUGUGGGACAUGGCUUCUGCGACCGACAUCACUUUACGCCGUGUCCUGGUUGGCCACCGGGCUGCCGUCAAUGUAGUAGACUUUGACGACAAGUACAUCGUGUCUGCCUCUGGUGACAGGACCAUCAAAGUCUGGAGCACGAGCACCUGUGAAUUUGUUCGUACUCUCAAUGGGCACAAGCGGGGCAUUGCCUGUCUCCAGUACAGGGAUCGCCUGGUUGUUAGUGGAUCAUCAGAUAAUACCAUUAGGCUCUGGGAUAUUGAAUGUGGUGCCUGUUUAAGAGUCCUAGAGGGACAUGAAGAAUUGGUCCGAUGCAUCCGGUUUGAUAACAAGAGGAUUGUCAGUGGGGCCUAUGAUGGGAAAAUUAAAGUUUGGGACUUGCAAGCUGCUCUUGACCCUCGAGCCCCAGCAAGCACAUUGUGUUUGCGCACAUUGGUGGAACAUUCUGGACGUGUGUUUCGGCUCCAGUUUGAUGAGUUUCAGAUCAUCAGCAGCUCCCAUGAUGACACUAUUUUGAUUUGGGAUUUCUUAAAUGUGCCUCCCAGUGCCCAGAAUGAGACCCGUUCUCCCUCCAGAACAUACACUUACAUCUCUAGAUAACAGUCUGCACUUUCACCCGUUUCAGGGUUUUCUAGUCUUGAACUACUGGCUACGUGGCUACCAAAUGCCUAAGGGAGUUCGUUCACAGCUGAGUUAUGAAGCUGGAAUUGGUUCUAGACGCUGGGUAGAUGCAAAGCAGCCUAACUCUUCAAGUACCGACAUUUCUCACCUCUGAUUCCGGCUCUCCUUUGAGAAGGAGACCUUAGCUUCCCCGGCUUCAAGUAGAACAGAAGCCCGUUUCCUUCCCUCAUCAGUGAAAAAAUCUAAUGUUUCAAAUGUAAAUUGUUCAUAGAAAAGGAACAUAGAAUCUGUUUUACAGAAGUAAAUCGACCGUCAAGAGAAGACUUGGCCUCUAAUUUAUAUUGCUUUGCACUUUGGUUUGAUAUUAAGAAACAGCAUUCUUCUUCAGUGAAAUUUUGGGUGCCAAACACCUACCCAGAAUGUCCAGGGCUUUCAUUUUCAAAAGUUAGCAUUCUCCUUUUGACCGUCCAAGUCAUUAUGAAUUCUGACUUGUUGUAUUAGGAACAUGUUGGACAGUGGAAAAUUUUCUCUGGAUUGUUUUAGUAAUAUUUUUGGGAUUAUACUUCCUUUCUGUACCAAUUUCUUUUAAUUUAAAGAACUAUAAGUCAGUUAUAUUAUCUACCAACAGGUAAUAUAGCUCUUUCUUUUAUUAACUGUUCUCUGUCCCCCAACCAUCUCCUGAUAUUUGGUAGAGUAACACCUUUAUACGUGUGCUUGCCUCCUAAUUUAAAAUACUGUAUUCGCAUGUAGAUAUAAUGUACAUAACAGUUUAACCUCAAAGUUGCUGGAGUCAGGGCCCCCUGUGCUUGAGACACUAAUACAGAGUGUGUUCGCACUUAGCCAUGGGCUGGGCUCAAGAACCUGAUACCUGGGUUGAUGUGGAUUACCUAGAACCCUUCCUGCAGUAUUCAUACAGUGUUUUUAUUUUGUUGUUGUCAUUGCGUGUGUGUGGUUUGUGUGUGUUUUUAAUGAGAAUCUUGUUUUAAAAUGUAAUUUCUAAGGUUUAACACCAAAAUGUUUUAUUUGUUGUGGAGUAUAUAUUAUACAAUAGAGAGGUACCUUAAACAUUUUUUGUUCUUAUUCUUUUUCUCAUAAGUACUCCUGAGUACAAGUGGUCACCUCCCAUAGUAUUCAUUUGGCUUCGCUGUCAAAAAUCAUUAUUCUGUGCAGUCGUGGCCCUGGGAAGGGGAAAUAAGAAGGCCCUGUUGACGGGCUGUCUUGGCUCUGGAAUUCAUGCAUCCUGGCCUUGCCAAGGUUCUGGCAGGGCCUGCUGGUGUGUUGGAGCCUGCAGGGCAGGUCAGGCUGGUUCAGAGGCCCAUGCUGAGGGGUGGGUGCUCUGAAGUGGAGUGAAGCCUCAAGCCCAUGAAUGCCACCCCAGUCAUCUCUGGUGUCAGCUGCUGCUGUGGCCCCAGCAGGUUCUCAAAGCUCCCAAGUCCUCCCUACGACACAGCCCAAAUGUGUAAAUGGCACUGUUGCCCUGACAGUGCAUGGAAAGGACGUUGGCAUCCAAUUGGCACUCCUUCUCCCUUAUUCAAUAUUAGGUUUGAUUUGCCCUUCGCCAUUGUUUCCAAAGAUCAAGGAAUGUCAAUAACAUUUUAAAGGACCAAUAAACAGCCUCCUAUAAAGUAAACCUCUUCCCGUGGAAGCACACUCUACUACUAAAGGGAAGGCCCUGGGCUCUGAUUUGUCCUUUGCAUUGAGAACGGUGUGGGGAUCAGUGUGUGUGUAUGUGAUUUGUUUAUUGAGUUGGCUUUGCUUUUUUAGUUUUUCUUUUAAAAAUAAAAUCCUUCCUUCCCAUGUUACUAAAUUAAUUUAUGUUUUUGAGAGGUUGAGUCUCAAAGUGUAAACAAUAAACCUCCAUUCAUAAGGUGGAUGUUGUAAGCUUGAUGGUGGUUGUGAAAGUGAUUUAGCUUUGACCACUUUUCAUCCUACAGCUUCAAUAUCAAACUGGUUAGGAAAGCCCAGGGGGAAGGGAGGGGGCAGGGGAGGAGGCAAUUCUGAAUGAAUGAAUGGAUUUUUUGUUGUUUUUGCAUGUUUAAUAUAGAAGUUCCCCUCGUUCCUUGGGAGAUGAUGGCCUUUGAAUAUGCAGACAACCUUUGAAUUGUGCCUACUAAAUUAUAGCAGGGGACUUUGGCACCCAAGGAGUUCUGACUUUCUGGGAUUAUAAUAGUAAUUCCCAGCCAUACUCUGGACUUUAUUUUGCUAACCAUAACUGAGCAAAUGUAAAUUACUGCUAUAUUAAUGUUUUAAAGCACUGGGAUAGUCUAAUUCUAACUUGUAAUUAAUUAUGUUUGCCAAUUAUCUGUUUGAAAUAAAUUUGUGUCUGAACAGCUAUUGAAACUGUUAAAUUGUACAGAUAUUAUUCAUGACAGCUUUGUACUGUGGAAUGUGCUUAAUAAAAAACAAAAAAGUUUGACUUUUGUCCAGUAAAUUGCUAAGUAAUGUCAAUAAAUCGAGUAUGGGUAUUAUGCAGUGCACCUAAUCUGGCUUCAUGCAAUUGUUACUUCAGCUACUGAUUCAAAGCCAAUACUCUUAAUAAAGUGUUGCAAUACUCUGA